UCAGUGAGGAGAUUCUAUGUAUCAACAGAAAGAACAAAGAUCAGGGCUGCCUAAUUGCUGACAUGAUGGGACUCACCGAGGGGGUGUUCCUGAUUCUGUCUGGCACUCAGUUCACACUGGGAAUUCUGGUCAAUUGUUUCAUUGAGUUGGUCAAUGGUAGCAGCUGGUUCAAGACCAAGAGAAUGUCUUUGUCUGACUUCAUCAUCACCACCCUGGCACUCUUGAGGAUCAUUCUGCUGUGUAUUAUCUUGACUGAUAGUUUUUUAAUAGAAUUCUCUCCCAACACACAUGAUUCAGGGAUAAUAAUGCAAAUUAUUGAUGUUUCCUGGACAUUUACAAACCAUCUGAGCAUUUGGCUUGCCACCUGUCUUGGUGUCCUCUACUGCCUGAAAAUCGCCAGUUUCUCUCACCCCACAUUCCUCUGGCUCAAGUGGAGAGUUUCUAGGGUGAUGGUAUGGAUGCUGUUGGGUGCACUGCUCUUAUCCUGUGGUAGUACCGCAUCUCUGAUCAAUGAGUUUAAGCUCUAUUCUGUCUUUAGGGGAAUUGAGGCCACCAGGAAUGUGACUGAACACUUCAGAAAGAAGAGGAGUGAGUAUUAUCUGAUCCAUGUUCUUGGGACUCUGUGGUACCUGCCUCCCUUAAUUGUGUCCCUGGCCUCCUACUCUUUGCUCAUCUUCUCCCUGGGGAGGCACACACGGCAGAUGCUGCAAAAUGGGACAAGCUCCAGAGAUCCAACCACUGAGGCCCACAAGAGGGCCAUCAGAAUCAUCCUUUCCUUCUUCUUUCUCUUCUUACUUUACUUUCUUGCUUUCUUAAUUGCAUCAUUUGGUAAUUUCCUACCAAAAACCAAGAUGGCUAAGAUGAUUGGCGAAGUAAUGACAAUGUUUUAUCCUGCUGGCCACUCAUUUAUUCUCAUUCUGGGGAACAGUAAGCUGAAGCAGACAUUUGUAGUGAUGCUCCGGUGUGAGUCUGGUCAUCUGAAGCCUGGAUCCAAGGGACCCAUUUUCUCUUAGAGUAACAGAGGGCAUGGGGUGGAGCCCUUGAGCCUUUUGGCCUGGCUCAAGACUACAGGACUCUUCCUGACCUUCCUAUGUUACCAGU